AGAACGAGUGGGAACGUAGCUGGUCGCAGAGGGCACCAGCGGCUGCAGGACUUCACCAAGGGACCCUGAGGCUCGUGAGCAGGGACCCGCGGUGCGGGUUAUGCUGGGGGCUCAGAUCACCGUAGACAACUGGACACUCAGGACCACGCCAUGGAGGAGCUGCAGGAUGAUUAUGAAGACAUGAUGGAGGAGAAUCUGGAGCAGGAGGAAUAUGAAGACCCAGACAUCCCCGAGUCCCAGAUGGAGGAGCCGGCAGCUCACGACACCGAGGCAACAGCCACAGACUACCACACCACAUCACACCCGGGUACCCACAAGGUCUAUGUGGAGCUGCAGGAGCUGGUGAUGGACGAAAAGAACCAGGAGCUGAGAUGGAUGGAGGCGGCGCGCUGGGUGCAACUGGAGGAGAACCUGGGGGAGAAUGGGGCCUGGGGCCGCCCGCACCUCUCUCACCUCACCUUCUGGAGCCUCCUAGAGCUGCGUAGAGUCUUCACCAAGGGUACUGUCCUCCUAGACCUGCAAGAGACCUCCCUGGCUGGAGUGGCCAACCAACUGCUAGACAGGUUUAUCUUUGAAGACCAGAUCCGGCCUCAGGACCGAGAGGAGCUGCUCCGGGCCCUGCUGCUUAAACACAGCCACGCUGGAGAGCUGGAGGCCCUGGGGGGUGUGAAGCCUGCAGUCCUGACACGCUCUGGGGAUCCUUCACAGCCUCUGCUCCCCCAACACUCCUCACUGGAGACACAGCUCUUCUGUGAGCAGGGAGAUGGGGGCACAGAAGGGCACUCACCAUCUGGAAUUCUGGAAAAGAUUCCCCCGGAUUCAGAGGCCACGUUGGUGCUAGUGGGCCGCGCCGACUUCCUGGAGCAGCCGGUGCUGGGCUUCGUGAGGCUGCAGGAGGCAGCGGAGCUGGAGGCGGUGGAGCUGCCGGUGCCUAUACGCUUCCUCUUUGUGUUGCUGGGACCUGAGGCCCCCCACAUCGAUUACACCCAGCUUGGCCGGGCUGCUGCCACCCUCAUGUCAGAGAGGGUGUUCCGCAUAGAUGCCUACAUGGCUCAGAGCCGAGGGGAGCUGCUGCACUCCCUAGAGGGCUUCCUGGACUGCAGCCUAGUGCUGCCUCCCACCGAUGCCCCCUCCGAGCAGGCACUGCUCAGUCUGGUGCCUGUGCAGAGGGAGCUACUUCGAAGGCGCUAUCAGUCCAGCCCUGCCAAGCCAGACUCCAGCUUCUACAAGGGCCUAGACUUAAAUGGGGGCCCAGAUGACCCUCUGCAGCAGACAGGCCAGCUCUUCGGGGGCCUGGUGCGUGAUAUCCGGCGCCGCUACCCCUAUUACCUGAGUGACAUCACAGAUGCAUUCAGCCCCCAGGUCCUGGCUGCCGUCAUCUUCAUCUACUUUGCUGCACUGUCACCCGCCAUCACCUUCGGCGGCCUCCUGGGAGAAAAGACCCGGAACCAGAUGGGAGUGUCGGAGCUGCUGAUCUCCACUGCAGUGCAGGGCAUUCUCUUCGCCCUGCUGGGGGCUCAGCCCCUGCUUGUGGUCGGCUUCUCAGGACCCCUGCUGGUGUUUGAGGAAGCCUUCUUCUCGUUCUGCGAGACCAACGGUCUAGAGUACAUCGUGGGCCGCGUGUGGAUCGGCUUCUGGCUCAUCCUGCUGGUGGUGUUGGUGGUGGCCUUCGAGGGUAGCUUCCUGGUCCGCUUCAUCUCCCGCUAUACCCAGGAGAUCUUCUCCUUCCUCAUUUCCCUCAUCUUCAUCUAUGAGACUUUCUCCAAGCUGAUCAAGAUCUUCCAGGACCACCCACUACAGAAGACUUAUAACUACAACGUGUUGAUGGUGCCCAAACCUCAGGGCCCCCUGCCCAACACAGCCCUCCUCUCCCUUGUGCUCAUGGCCGGUACCUUCUUCUUUGCCAUGAUGCUGCGCAAGUUCAAGAACAGCUCCUAUUUCCCUGGCAAGCUGCGUCGGGUCAUCGGGGACUUCGGGGUCCCCAUCUCCAUCCUGAUCAUGGUCCUGGUGGAUUUCUUCAUUCAGGAUACCUACACCCAGAAACUCUCGGUGCCUGAUGGCUUCAAGGUGUCCAACUCCUCAGCCCGGGGCUGGGUCAUCCACCCACUGGGCUUGCGUUCCGAGUUUCCCAUCUGGAUGAUGUUUGCCUCCGCCCUGCCUGCUCUGCUGGUCUUCAUCCUCAUAUUCCUGGAGUCUCAGAUCACCACGCUGAUUGUCAGCAAACCUGAGCGCAAGAUGGUCAAGGGCUCCGGCUUCCACCUGGACCUGCUGCUGGUAGUAGGCAUGGGUGGGGUGGCCGCCCUCUUUGGGAUGCCCUGGCUCAGUGCCACCACCGUGCGUUCCGUCACCCAUGCCAACGCCCUCACUGUCAUGGGCAAAGCCAGCACCCCAGGGGCUGCAGCCCAGAUCCAGGAGGUCAAAGAGCAGCGGAUCAGUGGACUCCUGGUCGCUGUGCUUGUGGGCCUGUCCAUCCUCAUGGAGCCCAUCCUGUCCCGCAUCCCCCUGGCUGUACUGUUUGGCAUCUUCCUCUACAUGGGGGUCACGUCGCUCAGCGGCAUCCAGCUCUUUGACCGCAUCUUGCUUCUGUUCAAGCCACCCAAGUAUCACCCAGAUGUGCCCUACGUCAAGCGGGUGAAGACCUGGCGCAUGCACUUAUUCACGGGCAUCCAGAUCAUCUGCCUGGCAGUGCUGUGGGUGGUGAAGUCCACGCCGGCCUCCCUGGCCCUGCCCUUCGUCCUCAUCCUCACUGUGCCGCUGCGGCGCGUCCUGCUGCCGCUCAUCUUCAGGAACGUGGAGCUUCAGUGUCUGGAUGCUGAUGAUGCCAAGGCAACCUUUGAUGAGGAGGAAGGUCGGGAUGAAUACGACGAAGUGGCCAUGCCUGUGUGAGGGGCGGGCCCAGGCCCUAGACCCUCCCCCACCAUUCCACAUCCCCACCUUCCAAGGAAAAGCAGAAGUUCAUGGGCACCUCAUGGACUCCAGGAUCCUCCUGGAGCAGCAGCUGAGGCCCCAGGGCUGUGGGUGGGGAAGGAAGGCGUGUCCAGGAGACCUUCCACAAAGGGUAGCCUGGCUUUUCUGGCUGGGGAUGGCCGAUGGGGCCCACAUUAGGGGGUUUGUUGCACAGUCCCUCCUGUUGCCACACUUUCACUGGGGAUCCCGUGCUGGAAGACUUAGAUCUGAGCCCUCCCUCUUCCCAGCACAGGCAGGGGUAGAAGCAAAGGCAGGAGGUGGGUGAGCGGGUGGGGUGCUUGCUGUGUGACCUUGGGCAAGUCCCUUGACCUUUCCAGCCUAUAUUUCCUCUUCUGUAAAAUGGGUAUAUUGAUGAUAAUACCCACAUUACAGGAUGGUUACUGAGGACCAAAGAUACAUGUAAAAUAGGGCUUUGUAAACUCCACAGGGACUGUUCUAUAGCAGUCAUCAUUUGUCUUUGAACGUACCCAAGGUCACAUAGCUGGGAUUUGAACUGAGCCGUGCAGCUGGGAUUUGAACCAGGCCUUCUGAUUUCAAGGUCCGAGCUCUGUCCUCUGUCAGUCAUGCGUCCACUUUCCCUUCCCCUGUGACUCCUCCCUUCCCCACUCUGCUCCCAGCCCCUACCUUGAGACCCUCUUCUCUGGGCCCAGAGAGAGGCGUCCUGGUGAGGACAAGGUACAGGCAAGGAUGAUCCAGGGAUUGGGCCUGGGACUCAGGCCUCCUAAGUGUUUGGUUCCUCCCUCCAAACACUCAUUAGUUCACUCAUUCAUUCAUUCCACAAACAUUUACUGAGGGCCCCGGAAUCAGUGGACUCCGAGGGGACUGAGACAAGCCCUGCCCUGGGGUGGGGGUGGGGGGCAAGGUACAGUUGAUUCUACAUUUGGAUAGGGAGUGGGGGAGGGUGGGAAGGUAGGGGCGGGAGAGUGAGGGGGUUUGUAAUUUAUUAAUUGCGUAUUUUCUAAGAGUUUUCAACAUAGUUUGGCUUCACACACAACUUCAGGCCCCUCAUUUGAGAGCCAUUAUCCUCAACUCCAUCUAAACUGAAUCUUGGGGAGAACCCAGAUCUGACCAAUUGGGGUAGGAGACAGCAGGCUCUCCAAGAACAUGGGCAAAUUUAUUUUUUUAUAAAACAAAAAGAUAAAAAGAGUUGAAAGACGUGAAAGUGGUGAGAGAUGGAGGAAACAGAAUCAGGAAGUGGUAGAAAAGAGAGGAGGUGGCUGGGCGCAGUGGCUCACGUUUGUAAUCCCAGCACUUUGGGAGGCCAAGUUGGGCGGAUCAUUUGAGGUCAGGAGUUUGAGACCAGCCUGGCCAACAUGGUGAAACCCCGUUACUACUAAAAAUACAAAAAUUAGCUGGGUGUCUCGUGGCAGGCACCUGUAAUCCCAGCUACUUAGAAGGCUGAGGCAAGAGAAUCACCUGAACCCAGGAGGUGGAGGUUGCAGUGAGCCAAGAUUGCACCACUGCACUCCAGCCUGGGCAACAGAGCGAGACCCUGUCUCAAAAAAAAAAAAAAAAAAAAAAAAAAAACGGAAGGAAACAUCAGCCUUGGGGGCCACAGACUCAACAUGUGUGUGUGGUGGGGUUCCAGCCCAACAUAGAGUAACAUUAUUUGUACCUCCCAGGCUAGCUCAGUCCAUGGGAGGCUCUCCUGUCCCUGAAAGCUGACACCCACCUUUCACCACUUCGCCCAUGCUACAGUUCAGUUUCCUCGUCUGUAAAAUGGGGAUGAUAAUGGUACCUACCUUGCAGUGUUGUUAUAAGGAUUAAAGGAGACAGUGCAAGAAAAGGCCUUGGUUGGUGAAGAGCCCAACCUCGGAGGGGAGCUGCUGGGAUCCUCCUUAUCUUGACUGGGAUGUCCCUGUCUCCCCCUCCCCUUGCUCCUUGAACAUGGCCAAGGAAAGUGAAAAACAAAAAUUAUUCACUCUGCUAGCACCCUUCCCCUUGAUGCCUGGGAAUAGGUUUUGCCAAUAAACGUAUCUGUGUUGGA